AGCUUAUCCACGCUCUCCGAUCUCGUGUCUGUUUCUCUUUCUCUCUCCCUCUCUUGCGCUGUCCCUCAUUCAUGCACUCUUCCAUCUUUUUGCCAUUGUGCCAGCUCAAUUUAAAUGUAUCUGCUCUGUAUCUGUUCAAGUGGAGAUAAUCCAUGCAAAUCAGGAGCCGUGGCUCUCAAUGCCUGGUUCACAGAGAGGACUCAGCUUGAGGAGGUCACUCGUUCACAGCCGCUCCUCCCAUUAUAUUUUUCCCCUUAUUGCAGAACUGCUGUAUGUAUACAGUGACUGAAAGGACUCAAUUUACUGCAACUGCUGCCUGGCUUUACUUACAACUUUUUUUUUUUUAUAAAGGAACUUACCUCCAUCUGUCUUUUCAAGCAGAAAUACUGUAAUCAAUCCAGACAGUUAUAUCUUCAGUUCCUCAGGUUUUAAUAAAGUUUCAGGGUAGAAAGGGUCCCUUUAACUCCUGAAGACAGUAAAUCACAGUCUGUGUGGUGGUUCUCAGAAGACACUUAAAGGACUGAACUGGAUGCUCUACAUAGCACCCUUGCCAAAAGGGUUCGGAAAUGACUUCCAGCUUCCCACAGUAAUAAAAUGGCACUGUUUGGCAUCUUCGAGGUUACAGACCACUUACUCUAAACUUCACAAAUGGUUCUGAAGAGUAUGGAGCCUACGUAGAUUCAUAAGAGCCCAAUGUUUCCAAAGGACAUUAAUUUUGAUUUCUCCAAUGAAGGCUUGUGGCUGUCCUUAUGCUUUACAAAACAUUACCAAAUCAGAGCCGAAAAGAAAACUGCAAACCUACACUUUUCCUGCUGAGAUUCCUAAAGUUAUAGAGUAAAAUGUCACCAAAAGGAAGCAUGUGAUUCAUUUCACUCUUGCUGUUGGAAUUUGAAGAGAGCUUGAUAACUGUGUUCUAUGUGGAUCCAGCAUUACAACUGAUAAGGGUAUUUAUGGCACAAUGAAAAAUUUCAUCUUUCCCAGAAUGAUAUGAAGAUCAAUGAUGCAGACUGAUGGUUUUGAUGAAGCUGGGCAUUUAUAACUAGAUUCAUUAAGGAAUACAAAGAAAAUACUUAAAGGGAUCAAUAAUGGUGUCUUCUGGUUGCAGAAUGCGAAGUCUGUGGUUUAUCAUUGUAAUCAGCUUCUUACCAAAUACAGAAGGUUUCAGCAGAGCAGCUUUACCAUUUGGGCUGGUGAGGCGAGAAUUAUCCUGUGAAGGUUAUUCUAUAGAUCUGCGAUGCCCGGGCAGUGAUGUCAUCAUGAUUGAGAGCGCUAACUAUGGUCGGACGGAUGACAAGAUUUGUGAUGCUGACCCAUUUCAGAUGGAGAAUACAGACUGCUACCUCCCCGAUGCCUUCAAAAUUAUGACUCAAAGGUGCAACAAUCGAACACAGUGUAUAGUAGUUACUGGGUCAGAUGUGUUUCCUGAUCCAUGUCCUGGAACAUACAAAUACCUUGAAGUCCAAUAUGAAUGUGUCCCUUACAUUUUUGUGUGUCCUGGGACCUUGAAAGCAAUUGUGGACUCACCAUGUAUAUAUGAAGCUGAACAAAAGGCGGGUGCUUGGUGCAAGGACCCUCUUCAGGCUGCAGAUAAAAUUUAUUUCAUGCCCUGGACUCCCUAUCGUACCGAUACUUUAAUAGAAUAUGCUUCUUUAGAAGAUUUCCAAAAUAGUCGCCAAACAACAACAUAUAAACUUCCAAAUCGAGUAGAUGGUACUGGAUUUGUGGUGUAUGAUGGUGCUGUCUUCUUUAACAAAGAAAGAACGAGGAAUAUUGUGAAAUUUGACUUGAGGACUAGAAUUAAGAGUGGCGAGGCCAUAAUUAACUAUGCCAACUACCAUGAUACCUCACCAUACAGAUGGGGAGGAAAGACUGAUAUCGACCUAGCAGUUGAUGAAAAUGGUUUAUGGGUCAUUUACGCCACUGAACAGAACAAUGGAAUGAUAGUUAUUAGCCAGCUGAAUCCAUACACUCUUCGAUUUGAAGCAACGUGGGAGACUGUAUACGACAAACGUGCCGCAUCAAAUGCUUUUAUGAUAUGCGGAGUCCUCUAUGUGGUUAGGUCAGUUUAUCAAGACAAUGAAAGUGAAACAGGCAAGAACUCAAUUGAUUACAUUUAUAAUACCCGAUUAAACCGAGGAGAAUAUGUAGAUGUUCCCUUCCCCAACCAGUAUCAGUAUAUUGCUGCAGUGGAUUACAAUCCAAGAGAUAACCAACUUUACGUGUGGAACAAUAACUUCAUUUUACGAUAUUCUCUGGAGUUUGGUCCACCUGAUCCUGCCCAAGUGCCUACCACAGCUGUGACAAUAACUUCUUCAGCUGAGCUGUUCAAAACCAUAAUAUCAACCACAAGCACUACUUCACAGAAAGGCCCCAUGAGCACAACUGUAGCUGGAUCACAGGAAGGAAGCAAAGGGACAAAACCACCUCCAGCAGUUUCUACAACCAAAAUUCCACCUAUAACAAAUAUUUUUCCCCUGCCAGAGAGAUUCUGUGAAGCAUUAGACUCCAAGGGGAUAAAGUGGCCUCAGACACAAAGGGGAAUGAUGGUUGAACGACCAUGCCCUAAGGGAACAAGAGGAACUGCCUCAUAUCUCUGCAUGAUUUCCACUGGAACAUGGAACCCUAAGGGCCCCGAUCUUAGCAACUGUACCUCACACUGGGUGAAUCAGCUGGCUCAGAAGAUCAGAAGCGGAGAAAAUGCUGCUAGUCUUGCCAAUGAACUGGCUAAACAUACCAAAGGGCCAGUGUUUGCUGGGGAUGUAAGUUCUUCAGUGAGAUUGAUGGAGCAGUUGGUGGACAUCCUUGAUGCACAGCUGCAGGAACUGAAACCUAGUGAAAAAGAUUCAGCUGGACGGAGUUAUAACAAGGCAAUUGUUGACACAGUGGACAACCUUCUGAGACCCGAAGCUUUGGAAUCAUGGAAACAUAUGAAUUCUUCUGAACAAGCACAUACUGCAACAAUGUUACUCGAUACAUUGGAAGAAGGAGCUUUUGUCCUAGCUGACAAUCUUUUAGAACCAACAAGGGUCUCAAUGCCCACAGAAAAUAUUGUCCUGGAAGUUGCCGUACUCAGUACAGAAGGACAGAUCCAAGACUUUAAAUUUCCUCUGGGCAUCAAAGGAGCAGGCAGCUCAAUCCAACUGUCCGCAAAUACCGUCAAACAGAACAGCAGGAAUGGGCUUGCAAAGUUGGUGUUCAUCAUUUACCGGAGCCUGGGACAGUUCCUUAGUACAGAAAAUGCAACCAUUAAACUGGGUGCUGAUUUUAUUGGUCGUAAUAGCACCAUUGCAGUGAACUCUCACGUCAUUUCAGUUUCAAUCAAUAAAGAGUCCAGCCGAGUAUACCUGACUGAUCCUGUGCUUUUUACCCUGCCACACAUUGAUCCUGACAAUUAUUUCAAUGCAAACUGCUCCUUCUGGAACUACUCAGAGAGAACUAUGAUGGGAUAUUGGUCUACCCAGGGCUGCAAGCUGGUUGACACUAAUAAAACUCGAACAACGUGUGCAUGCAGCCACCUAACCAAUUUUGCAAUUCUCAUGGCCCACAGGGAAAUUGCAUAUAAAGAUGGCGUUCAUGAAUUACUUCUUACAGUCAUCACCUGGGUGGGAAUUGUCAUUUCCCUUGUUUGCCUGGCUAUCUGCAUCUUCACCUUCUGCUUUUUCCGUGGCCUACAGAGUGACCGAAAUACUAUUCACAAGAACCUUUGUAUCAACCUUUUCAUUGCUGAAUUUAUUUUCCUAAUAGGCAUUGAUAAGACAAAAUAUGCGAUUGCAUGCCCAAUAUUUGCAGGACUUCUACACUUUUUCUUUUUGGCAGCUUUUGCUUGGAUGUGCCUAGAAGGUGUGCAGCUCUACCUAAUGUUAGUUGAAGUUUUUGAAAGUGAAUAUUCAAGGAAAAAAUAUUACUAUGUUGCUGGUUACUUGUUUCCUGCCACAGUGGUUGGAGUUUCAGCUGCUAUUGACUAUAAGAGCUAUGGAACAGAAAAAGCUUGCUGGCUUCAUGUUGAUAACUACUUUAUAUGGAGCUUCAUUGGACCUGUUACCUUCAUUAUUCUGCUAAAUAUUAUCUUCUUGGUGAUCACAUUGUGCAAAAUGGUGAAGCAUUCAAACACUUUGAAACCAGAUUCUAGCAGGUUGGAAAACAUUAAGUCUUGGGUGCUUGGCGCUUUCGCUCUUCUGUGUCUUCUUGGCCUCACCUGGUCCUUUGGGUUGCUUUUUAUUAAUGAGGAGACUAUUGUGAUGGCAUAUCUCUUCACUAUAUUUAAUGCUUUCCAGGGAGUGUUCAUUUUCAUCUUUCACUGUGCUCUCCAAAAGAAAGUACGAAAAGAAUAUGGCAAGUGCUUCAGACACUCAUACUGCUGUGGAGGCCUCCCAACUGAGAGUCCCCACAGUUCAGUGAAGGCAUCAACCACCAGAACCAGUGCUCGCUAUUCCUCUGGCACACAGAGUCGUAUAAGAAGAAUGUGGAAUGAUACUGUGAGAAAACAAUCAGAAUCUUCUUUUAUCUCAGGUGACAUCAAUAGCACUUCAACACUUAAUCAAGGAAUGACUGGCAAUUACCUACUAACAAACCCUCUUCUUCGACCCCACGGCACUAACAACCCCUAUAACACAUUGCUCGCUGAAACAGUUGUAUGUAAUGCCCCUUCAGCUCCUGUAUUUAACUCACCAGGACAUUCACUGAACAAUGCCAGGGAUACAAGUGCCAUGGAUACUCUACCGCUAAAUGGUAAUUUUAACAACAGCUACUCGCUGCACAAGGGUGACUAUAAUGACAGCGUGCAAGUUGUGGACUGUGGACUAAGUCUGAAUGAUACUGCUUUUGAGAAAAUGAUCAUUUCAGAAUUAGUGCACAACAACUUACGGGGCAGCAGCAAGACUCACAACCUCGAGCUCACGCUACCAGUCAAACCUGUGAUUGGAGGUAGCAGCAGUGAAGAUGAUGCUAUUGUGGCAGAUGCUUCAUCUUUAAUGCACAGCGACAACCCAGGGCUGGAGCUCCAUCACAAAGAACUCGAGGCACCACUUAUUCCUCAGCGGACUCACUCCCUUCUGUACCAACCCCAGAAGAAAGUGAAGUCCGAGGGAACUGACAGCUAUGUCUCCCAACUGACAGCAGAGGCUGAAGAUCACCUACAGUCCCCCAACAGAGACUCUCUUUAUACAAGCAUGCCCAAUCUUAGAGACUCUCCCUAUCCGGAGAGCAGCCCUGACAUGGAAGAAGACCUCUCUCCCUCCAGGAGGAGUGAGAAUGAGGACAUUUACUAUAAAAGCAUGCCAAAUCUUGGAGCUGGCCAUCAGCUUCAGAUGUGCUACCAGAUCAGCAGGGGCAAUAGUGAUGGUUAUAUAAUCCCCAUUAACAAAGAAGGGUGUAUUCCAGAAGGAGAUGUUAGAGAAGGACAAAUGCAGCUGGUUACAAGUCUUUAAUCAUACAGCUAAGGAAUUCCAAGGGCCACAUGCGAGUAUUAAUAAAUAAAGACACCAUUGGCCUGACGCAGCUCCCUCAAACUCUGCUUGAAGAGAUGACUCUUGACCUGUGGUUCUCUGGUGUAAAAAAGAUGACUGAACCUUGCAGUUCUGUGAAUUUUUAUAAAACAUACAAAAACUUUGUAUAUACACAGAGUAUACUAAAGUGAAUUAUUUGUUACAAAGAAAAGAGAUGCCAGCCAGGUAUUUUAAGAUUCUGCUGCUGUUUAGAGAAAUUGUGAAACAAGCAAAACAAAACUUUCCAGCCAUUUUACUGCAGCAGUCUGUGAACUAAAUUUGUAAAUAUGGCUGCACCAUUUUUGUAGGCCUGCAUUGUAUUAUAUACAAGACGUAGGCUUUAAAAUCCUGUGGGACAAAUUUACUGUACCUUACUAUUCCUGACAAGACUUGGAAAAGCAGGAGAGAUAUUCUGCAUCAGUUUGCAGUUCACUGCAAAUCUUUUACAUUAAGGCAAAGAUUGAAAACAUGCUUAACCACUAGCAAUCAAGCCACAGGCCUUAUUUCAUAUGUUUCCUCAACUGUACAAUGAACUAUUCUCAUGAAAAAUGGCUAAAGAAAUUAUAUUUUGUUCUAUUGCUAGGGUAAAAUAAAUACAUUUGUGUCCAACUGAAAUAUAAUUGUCAUUAAAAUAAUUUUAAAGAGUGAAGAAAAUAUUGUGAAAAGCUCUUGGUUGCACAUGUUAUGAAAUGUUUUUUCUUACACUUUGUCAUGGUAAGUUCUACUCAUUUUCACUUCUUUUCCACUGUAUACAGUGUUCUGCUUUGACAAAGUUGGUCUUUAUUACUUACAUUUAAAUUUCUUAUUGCCAAAAGAACGUGUUUUAUGGGGAGAAACAAACUCUUUGAAGCCAGUUAUGUCAUGCCUUGCACAAAAGUGAUGAAAUCUAGAAAAGAUUGUGUGUCACCCCUGUUUAUUCUUGAACAGAGGGCAAAGAGGGCACUGGGCACUUCUCACAAACUUUCUAGUGAACAAAAGGUGCCUAUUCUUUUUUAAAAAAAUAAAAUAAAACAUAAAUAUUACUCUUCCAUAUUCCUUCUGCCUAUAUUUAGUAAUUAAUUUAUUUUAUGAUAAAGUUCUAAUGAAAUGUAAAUUGUUUCAGCAAAAUUCUGCUUUUUUUUCAUCCCUUUGUGUAAACCUGUUAAUAAUGAGCCCAUCACUAAUAUCCAGUGUAAAGUUUAACACGGUUUGACAGUAAAUAAAUGUGAAUUUUUUCAAGUAGUUAACAUGUGAACUUUUAUGUAUGAUACAUAAUUGGCUUUAACAUGUUGGUCCAUUCCCACCUUGGUUUAAGUAACGUCAUACCAAAGUCCAUGGAUAUAUGAAAGGAUACAAUUAAGUUGCCUGUUUGUUCUUUAUGCUGAAAGGAAUAUAUGUCUUCCAAUUGCCCACUACAUAUGCACAAAAUCUGCUGGAUAAGUUUUAAGAGGGAUAUAUUCUGAAAGCAUUUUUGUUUGUUGCAUUGUACCAGGACUAAAAAAAGAAGGAUUGGAAGUUCUGCCAUCAAAUUUGGGUAUCAUAAAAAGUUUUUAACUGAUUUUUCAGCAGUAUUGGGAAGUUUCUUAAACAUACUUUAAGGAUUAUAAAUAUCCCUAUAGACAGCUGUGAAUACCAAUAUACAUUACCCUGGAAAAGUUUUACUCCAAGUUCAAAAAUCAUAUAAUUGAAUAUCAAGAAAUAGAUGUUUUCUGUUUGUAUCAUAAGCAUUUAUAGAAAAUUAUUCUAAAGCUUAAUGGUUUGCUAUAAUUCUCAAAUACUACCACUAGCUUAUAAAUCACUUUUAUGUGGACACACACAUGCCUAUUGAAUUUAAAAAGGAAUGAGAUUUAAAAAUUAAGUGCAUAUAUAUAAUAUACAUAUAUAUAUAUAUAUAUAUAUAUAUAUAUUUUUUUUUUUUUUUUUUUUUUUUUUUUUUUUGGGACAGAGUGUCCCUCUGUCACCCAGGCUGGAGUGCAGUAGUGUGAUCUCGGCUCACUGCAACCUCCGCCUCCCAGGUUCUCAAACAGAUUUAACAAUCCUCUGAGAAUGGUACUCAUUUAUUUGGCUAAAAUUCUUCAGGGAUUUAUAAACUACUUGCUAAAGGAGGGCAUUAGAUAAUCAAGUAUUUUUAAUUUUCCAUCUUGUUAUACUUUUUAUUUUAAAUGCCUAAAACCAUACAGUAUUGUGUGAUGUGUAAUUCCUAGUAUACAAGCUACCUAGAGUCAGGCUGGUUCAGUAAUAAAUUUUUUUAAAGGCAACACUGAUUAUUCAGUUAGUCCUAUUUCUUUCUCUUGAGGCAGUUCUCAAAACUCUAAAGACAUGAACACUGCAUCGUACCUAAAUGGCUACUGUUCUCUAACGUCUUUAUCCUAUGGAUUCAAUUUGGAAGCCAUCAUUGAUCUUUGGCAUCAAAAGAAAAGUCAUUUUUAAAGCAUUUCUUUUCAAAAAUAUAUAAAUAUUGCCUUAAAUUCCAUCUAGGAUUCCCUUAGUACAAGGUAGUUUCUUAGGUUUGUAAUUACUAAACUACUGACUGUUUUAAUGCAGAUGCGUUAUUGUAUUUAUUAACCCAGUUUCUUUGGGUCUGCCUAGACUUCACCUGAAUGUACAGUUUUCACAUUCUUGAUUGUUUCUCUUUGUGAUAGUCACAACUGUGAACUUAUAAAGUCACAUUUUUAAAGUUCUUCCUAGAGACAUUCACUCUGUCUUUAUUAAAAAUAAUAAUAAUAAUAAUAAACGUUAUCUUGUUGGCCA